GUUUUAAUGCUAUAUCAGAUUUAAGUUGCAGCUUAUAUUUUUUCUUUAAACCUAUUUGCUUUAAUUGCCUUUCACAAAAGAAUUAAUAAUGUAUAUGGCAGAUGAUAAAGGUAAAAUUUAGAGUAGUCAUUCCAGAAUAAUCAUGAGUGUAUGAAAGCAGAAAUUUUCCCAGUAAUGAGUUUGUUCACAUGAGCAUGAAACAAGUAUCUUGGUAAGUAUCCAAAAAAAGCACAGCUGUGGAUUUAUCCUUUUGGAGUAACUAUAAAACAAGGGUGGAGAUUUUAAAUAAAUGAAUUUUUUCCAAGAGUAUAUUUCAUUAUGUGUGCCAGAUCAAAUUAAUUAUACAGCAGAGCUGAAUUUUUGAAUAUGUUCUAAGCAUAUGUCAGUUUCUCAAAGAUAUUUCCGUAGACCACCCCGGCCUGAAGAGCACCACCCGAGUUAUCCUGUCCUCUUUGUUUUUUCAUGUUUCUUUCUUCCCACUGCCCCUGAGGUUUUCUUAUUCAUUUAUGUAGCUAUUUGUUUAUUUUUGCUGCUGUGAGAUUAGGAACUUUUUCUAUCUUGAUCCAUUCUCUUUCCCCAGUAUCUUAUAGUGCUUACUACUUGUGAAUGAAGAAACAAACUGGGUUUUAUUUUAUAGUACUCUAUAAAAUGGGGUCCUCAUGUGUAACAGUAUAUAAUGUUUAUGUCCAUUUUCUCGAACUUGAAGAAUUUUUGUAGCUAAAACCAAUUAUGUCUAUAUACACACCUAUAUGUGAAAUUCUUAGAACAGUGCCUGAUUCAUAUUAAGUAGUCAAUAAAUGCUACCAAUUAUGAAUAAAACCAUUUGCUUUUAUAAUAUAUGAUUUGCAUUUUACUUGAUCCUGAGUUACUAUGAUGUAUGUUUGGACUUUAUUUGAUAAUGAAUCCUUAGUUGAAAUGCCACCCCUAAUUAUUUCUUCAUUUUCAGAAAUACGUGGCAUCAAAAGACAGACUUCUGGUGUUGAGGAUAUAUUUUCUGUUAGGGACUUUUUAGGGGUGAAAAUGUAAAAUAGGAUUCCUGAAUUUAUACAUUUGUUUAAAAUUGUAUCUUUUAGAUACUUGGUAUGAUGGGGUAAAAAGACAUGGCAUAAUUACAGAUGCCAGUUGAUGCAAUGCCUUAGUGUGUUUAUUUCAGUUGAUAAGCUUUACUGCUGGUUCAGAUUACAAUUUUGUAAGGUGAAGUGUAUCACUUUUAACCCCCCUUUGUUUAGAUUUUCAUUGAUUUUAUUAAGAAAACCAGAUCAUCUUUCUCCUACGAUUUAUUCUUUCAGGAAACAAAGCUAUGUCCUGGGCCAACCCCAUGGAGAAUAUUGUCACCCUUUCAUGCCUGUUGGUACCAAAAGAAAAGUUGUCACAUGGAUGCCUAAGUAGAUAAUAUCUUAUUAAAAUGAGAAAUGCAUAAGCUAGAGAAAAGCAUUUCCUACUGUGUAGACGAUAGUCCUAAUGUGAGGCCAGCUAUUUCUUUCUCUACUGUGUAGACCGAUAGUCCUAAUGUGAGGCCAGCUAUUUCUUUCUCUGCAAUAGCAGGAGUUGUGGGGUGAGAGGAGGUUUAAUCUUUAUAAAGCCAUCUGGUGAUGAAUCAGCCAGCCAAUUGCCAGACCAUAAGGAUAGACUGCCCUUAACAUGUGUUUUAGCUCAAGUAAUUGUAUACACUGACUAUCAUUUAUAGAAUAAUGAUUUUUUCUCAGGCUUAAUAAUCUGAGUAAACCAGUUUCUUUUUAUGGGUGAUAUGGUGCACUAUUUUGUAGUUCUCUUGUUAUACUGUCAUAUAUCAAGUGCACUUACUUAUUAUUGCCUGUCUCAACUUAAGUAUUAUAGUAAUUAACAUCAUUCAGACCCCUCUUGCCAUCAUUCCUCGAUUUGAAUGAUAUGUGAAUAGGAACAACGUUUUAAAAUAUAUAUAUAUAUAUAUAUAUAUAUUUUUUUUUUGAGAUGGAGUCUUGCUCUGUUGCCCAGUCUGGAGUACAGUGGCGUGAUCUUGGCUCACUGUAAGCUCCGCCUCCUGGGUUCACACCAUUCUCCUGCCUCAGCCUCCUAAUUAGCUGGGACUACAGGCGCCUGCCACCACAAUCGGCUAAUUUUUUGUAUUUUUAAUAGAGACAGGGUUUCACCAUGUUAGCCAGGAUGGUCUUGAUCUCCUGACCUCGUGAUCUGCCCGCCUCGGCCUCCCAAAGUGCUGGGAUUACAGGCGUGAGCCACCGCGCCUGGCCUGAAAUAUUUUUAAAAAGCAGUAAAAUGUAUGUAAUUUUAAACCUGUGUAGUGAAGCUGUGUGCUCUGCUCAAUAGCUGCAGAGUUUUUCUUUGUUUCAUGUUUAUUUAGAAUGUAAAACUUAGAUAUUUACAUUUUAGUCCAUUAAAUCAUGAAAAGAACUCUGAUUUAGCAGGAAAGUCAGUUUUUAAAGUUAAUGAUAGCUUUAAAUGUAAAUGUAAUGAUAGUUCCAUGUAAAUGGAACUGUGAUGCUGGGCCAGUGUUCACAUCCAUCUGACACCCAAGUGUCUGAGCUUUCAACUUUUCUCAGAUUGCUAGUGAAAACAGCUUUAUGUGACAAAAAGAUAAAGAAUAAGAAAGAGACAACCGAAGAGGACUAUAACUAGGAUUUUUUAAUGGCUAGAUUGAAUUGCUGUCAAAGGUUAGAUGAUUAAUUUCACCUCCUGCCCCUGGAAAUUUCUAGGUUAUCCUCACUUCAAGACUUGUAGCAGCUCCAAAGCUACUCAUUCAUUGAAAAAUAGCUUGUCAAAUGCUCACUGUAGAUGAAACAUUGGGGUAGGCUCAAGGGAUACAAAGAUGAAAAAGUGUCUCUGUAUUUCAGCUCUGUGCUGGUUUAGAAUGAUACCAUCCCUACCGUCACCAUCCAUGUCUGGAGUAAUGACAACCUCCUGUUGUUCUAGUAACACCCUAGGUUUAUCUCUGUCAUGGCAUCUACUACCAUUCCCUGCAGUAGUGAGUUCCUUGAGGCAAGAUAUUUUUGUUUGUUUUAUCUUUAUGUGUCCUUGAUCCUCAGAGUGUCUGGAUUCCGCAGGCUUCUCAAUAGCUGUUGAAAGAAGGGAGGAAUGGAGGAAGACAGUUUUGCUGCCUUCAAAGAGCUCAUCAACUUGAGACUUGGCCAGGAAGUAUAUAUUCUGAACCAGGGAAAGAAAUGCUAAAAACCAAAUUGACAAAGUAGACAGAUGGAAGACCAACAACAUCUGCAUUAAGAAGAUGACGUAGCUUUGCCAAAGACUUAGAAGCUAAGCAGAAAAUGAGCUUAACAUCCUGGUUUUUGGUGAGCAGUGGAGGCACUCGCCACAGGCUGCCACGAGAAAUGAUUUUUGUUGGAAGAGAUGACUGUGAGCUCAUGUUGCAGUCUCGUAGUGUGGAUAAGCAACACGCUGUCAUCAACUAUGAUGCGUCUACGGAUGAGCAUUUAGUGAAGGAUUUGGGCAGCCUCAAUGGGACUUUUGUGAAUGAUGUAAGGAUUCCGGAACAGACUUAUAUCACCUUGAAACUUGAAGAUAAGCUGAGAUUUGGAUAUGAUACAAAUCUUUUCACUGUAGUACAAGGAGAAAUGAGGGUCCCUGAAGAAGCUCUUAAGCAUGAGAAGUUUACCAUUCAGCUUCAGUUGUCCCAAAAAUCUUCAGAAUCAGAAUUAUCCAAAUCUGCAAGUGCCAAAAGCAUAGAUUCAAAGGUAGCAGACGCUGCUACUGAAGUGCAGCACAAAACUACUGAAGCACUGAAAUCCGAGGAAAAAGCCAUGGAUAUUUCUGCUAUGCCCCGUGGUACUCCAUUAUAUGGGCAGCCGUCAUGGUGGGGGGAUGAUGAGGUGGAUGAAAAAAGAGCUUUCAAGACAAAUGGCAAACCUGAAGAAAAAAACCAUGAAGCUGGAACAUCAGGGUGCGGCAUAGAUGCCAAGCAAGUUGAGGAACAAUCUGCAGCUGCAAAUGAAGAAGUACUUUUUCCUUUCUGUAGGGAACCAAGUUAUUUUGAAAUCCCUACAAAAGAAUUCCAGCAACCAUCACAAAUAACAGAAAGCACUAUUCAUGAAAUCCCAACAAAAGACACGCCAAGUUCCCAUAUAACAGGUGCAGGGCAUGCUUCAUUUACCAUUGAAUUUGAUGACAGUACCCCAGGGAAGGUAACUAUUAGAGACCAUGUGACAAAGUUUACUUCUGAUCAGCGCCACAAGUCCAAGAAGUCUUCUCCUGGAACUCAAGACUUGCUGGGGAUUCAAACAGGAAUGAUGGCACCCGAAAACAAAGUUGCUGACUGGCUAGCACAAAACAACCCUCCUCAAAUGCUAUGGGAAAGAACAGAAGAGGAUUCUAAAAGCAUUAAAAGUGAUGUUCCAGUGUACUUGAAAAGGUUGAAAGGAAAUAAACAUGAUGAUGGUACGCAAAGUGAUUCAGAGAACGCUGGGGCUCACAGGCGCUGUAGCAAACGUGCAACUCUUGAGGAACACUUAAGACGCCACCAUUCAGAACACAAAAAGCUACAGAAGGUCCAGGCUACUGAAAAGCAUCAAGACCAAGCUGUUGUAAGUCAAACUGCUUUUAUGAUUGCAUUCUUUGAUGAAGACAAUCCCAGAAAAAGAAGGUCGUAUUCUUUUACUCAAAGUGCGGGAAUCUUGUGUCAGGAAACUACAUAUUCAACACCACAUACAAAACUUGAGAAAGCAAAGUCUCCAACAGCAGAUGCCAAAGUGGUUUCUUUGUCUUUACAGACUAGCUCUGCGCAUCACAGAGGGGGGCAUGGUGUUCCACAUGGGAAAUUGUUAAAACAGAAAUCAGAGGAGCCAUCGGUGUCAAUACCCUUCCUACAAACUGCAUUAUUAAGAAGUUCAGGGAGUCUUGGGCACAGACCAAGCCAGGAGAUGGAUAAAAUGUUAAAAAAUCAAGCAACUUCUGCUACUUCUGAAAAGGAUAAUGAUGAUGACCAAAGUGACAAGGGUACUUAUACCAUUGAGUUAGAGAAUCCCAACAGUGAGGAAGUGGAAGCAAGAAAAAUGAUUGACAAGGUGUUUGGAGUAGAUGACAAUCAGGAUUAUAAUAGGCCUGUUAUCAACGAAAAACAUAAAGAUCUAAUAAAAGAUUGGGCUCUCAGUUCUGCUGCAGCAGUAAUGGAAGAAAGAAAACCACUGACUACAUCUGGAUUUCACCACUCAGAGGAAGGCACAUCUUCAUCUGGAAGCAAACGUUGGGUUUCACAGUGGGCUAGUUUGGCUGCCAAUCAUACAAGGCAUGAUCAAGAAGAAAGGAUAAUGGAAUUUUCUGCACCUCUUCCUUUAGAGAAUGAGACAGAGAUCAGUGAGUCUGGCAUGACAGUGAGAAGUACUGGCUCUGCAACUUCCUUGGCUAGCCAGGGAGAGAGAAGGAGACGAACUCUUCCCCAGCUUCCAAAUGAAGAAAAGUCUCUUGAGAGCCACAGAGCAAAGGUUGUAACACAGAGGUCAGAGAUAGGAGAAAAACAAGACACAGAACUUCAGGAGAAAGAAACACCUACACAGGUAUACCAGAAAGAUAAACAAGAUGCUGACAGACCCUUGAGUAAAAUGAACAGGGCAGUAAAUGGAGAGACUCUCAAAACUGGUGGAGAUAAUAAAACCCUACUUCACUUAGGCAGCUCUGCUCCUGGAAAAGAGAAAAGUGAAACUGAUAAGGAAACUUCUUUGGUAAAGCAAACAUUAGCAAAACUUCAACAACAAGAACAAAGGGAGGAGGCUCAGUGGACACCUACUAAAUUGUCUUCCAAAAAUGUUUCAGGUCAGACAGAUAAAUGUAGGGAGGAAACUUUUAAACAAGAAUCACAACCUCCAGAAAAAAAUUCAGGACAUUCUACAAGCAAAGGAGACAGAGUGGCACAAAGUGAGAGCAAGAGAAGAAAAGCUGAGGAAAUUCUGAAAAGUCAGACUCCAAAGGGAGGAGACAAGAAGGAAUCCUCCAAGUCAUUAGUGCGACAAGGGAGCUUCACUAUAGAAAAACCCAGCCCAAACAUACCCAUAGAACUUAUUCCCCAUAUAAAUAAACAGACUUCCUCUACUCCUUCUUCUUUAGCAUUAACAUCUGCAAGUAGAAUACGAGAAAGAAGUGAGUCUUUGGAUCCUGAUUCUAGUAUGGACACAACCCUUAUUCUAAAAGACACAGAAGCAGUAAUGGCUUUUCUAGAAGCUAAACUACGUGAAGAUAAUAAAACUGAUGAAGGACCAGAUACUCCCAGUUAUAAUAGAGACAAUUCUAUUUCACCAGAAUCUGAUGUAGAUACAGCUAGUACAAUCAGUCUGGUUACUGGAGAAACUGAAAGAAAGUCAACCCAAAAGCGAAAGAGUUUCACUAGCCUCUAUAAAGAUAGGUGUUCCACAGGUUCUCCUUCCAAAGAUGUUACAAAAUCAUCAUCUUCAGGUGCUAGGGAAAAAAUGGAAAAGAAAACAAAAAGUCGUUCCACAGAUGUGGGUUCAAGAGCAGAUGGUCGUAAAUUUGUUCAGUCCAGUGGGAGAAUAAGACAGCCCUCAGUAGACUUAACAGAUGAUGACCAAACCUCUAGUGUACCUCAUUCUGCCAUCUCUGAUAUUAUGUCAUCUGAUCAAGAAACUUACUCUUGUAAACCUCAUGGACGGACUCCACUUACCUCAGCUGAUGAGCAUGUACAUUCCAAACUGGAAGGAAGUAAAGUAACGAAAUCUAAGACUUCUCCGGUGGUAUCUGGUUCAUCUAGUAAAUCAACCACCCUUCCAAGGCCACGACCUACCAGGACUUCCCUCUUGCGCAGAGCACGACUUGGUGAAGCUUCAGACAGUGAACUUGCUGAUGCUGACAAAGCAUCUGUUGCUUCUGAAGUAUCCACAACAAGUUCUACAUCAAAACCUCCCACAGGAAGGCGUAACAUCUCUCGGAUUGAUUUAUUGGCUCAGCCUCGUAGAACACGACUUGGCUCACUGUCAGCUCGUAGUGACUCUGAAGCAACAAUUUCUAGAAGUAGUGCCUCUUCGAGGACCGCAGAAGCCAUCAUUAGAAGUGGAGCCAGACUAGUACCAUCAGAUAAAUUUUCUCCUAGAAUUAGAGCUAACAGUAUCUCUCGACUCUCAGACUCCAAGGUCAAAAGUAUGACCUCAGCUCAUGGCUCUGCUUCAGUAAAUUCAAGAUGGAGGCGCUUUCCUACUGAUUAUGCUUCCACCUCAGAAGAUGAAUUUGGAUCAAACCGUAAUUCCCCUAAACAUACCCGUCUACGUACUUCUCCAGCCCUGAAAACCACUCGCUUGCAGAGCGCUGGAUCAGCAAUGCCUACUAGUUCUUCAUUCAAACACCGGAUUAAAGAGCAGGAAGACUACAUCCGAGAUUGGACUGCUCAUCGAGAAGAGAUAGCCAGGAUCAGCCAAGAUCUUGCUCUCAUUGCUCGGGAGAUCAACGAUGUAGCAGGAGAGAUAGAUUCAGUGACUUCAUCAGGCACUGCCCCUAGUACCACAGUAAGCACUGCUGCCACCACCCCUGGCUCUGCCAUAGACACUAGAGAAGAGGUAGGAGAUCUUCAUGGAGAAAUGCAUAAGUUGGUUGAUCGUGUUUUUGAUGAAAGCCUCAACUUCCGAAAGAUUCCUCCAUUAGUUCAUUCCAAAACACCAGAAGGAAACAACGGUCGAUCUGGUGAUCCAAGACCUCAAGCAGCAGAGCCUCCCGAUCACUUAACAAUUACAAGGCGGAGAACCUGGAGCAGGGAUGAAGUCAUGGGAGAUAAUCUGCUGCUGUCAUCCGUCUUUCAGUUCUCUAAGAAGAUAAGACAAUCUAUAGAUAAGACAGCUGGAAAGAUCAGAAUAUUAUUUAAAGACAAAGAUCGGAAUUGGGAUGACAUAGAAAGCAAAUUAAGAGCCGAAAGUGAAGUCCCUAUUGUGAAAACCUCAAGCAUGGAGAUUUCUUCUAUCUUACAGGAACUGAAAAGAGUAGAAAAGCAGCUGCAAGCAAUCAAUGCUAUGAUUGAUCCUGAUGGAACUUUGGAGGCUCUGAACAACAUGGGAUUUCCCAGUGCUAUGUUGCCAUCUCCACCGAAACAGAAGUCCAGCCCUGUGAAUAACCACCACAGCCCGGGUCAGACACCAACACUUGGCCAACCAGAAGCUAGGGCUCUUCAUCCUGCUGCUGUUUCAGCCGCAGCUGAAUUUGAGAAUGCUGAAUCUGAGGCUGAUUUCAGUAUACAUUUCAAUAGAUUCAACCCCGAUGGGGAAGAGGAAGAUGUUACAGUACAAGAAUGACUUUCUCUUGAUUGUUGAAAAAUCAUUACCUGUGGAAUGGCUAGGAAUAUUGGAAGCAGCAUAGUGUUGAUGUACGCAAAACAAGACAGCUUGGUCAGCUACAAUCUUGGAAUCCCUGUCUUCUUAAUUUUAUUUAUUUAUUUUUGACGUAUAAUGUAGUAUAUCAAUCCUUUCAAACUAUUUAGAUAACCACUUGAUGCACAAAUAGGAAAAAGCAGAUUGUGGCAGUGUCGCCUUUUGUGGUUUUAUGAUUUUCAAAUUGAAUUUAAUGAUUACACCCUUUCCCUUCAUAGAUCUUUUUUCUUUUUUUUAAGCCAUGCUGUGACCUACAAGCAAACUAAAUAGCCAACAUUUCUGAACCCCUAAGUCUCCUGUGCCAAGCUGCUCCCUGAAAUGGACUUCUUCAUCUGUACAGAUUUGUUAAACCAUUCUAUUUGCUUCUUAAUAAUAGGAUUUAUAUUAGUACUCAUUACCAUUGGACACAAUGACAUAAGUACUCUCCACAGUAAAGCAGACCUUUCACAACAGUCACUCUGUGUCCUAAAAUUUUCCAACAUAGAUGUGAUUUAUAUAACUUUGUUGAUACGUAAAUUGUCUUGGGGUUUACGGAAAUUAACUAUUAUGUUUGCACUAAGAUUUGCUGGGAGUGGUAGGUGGACAUAUCUAUAUAUCAAUAAGGACUAACCGUCUUUUUUGUACAUAGGAGAUUGAUAAUACUGUAUUUGUUUUAAGCCCACAGUGUUUUACUCCACUUUCAAAAAGAUCAAUUUGGCACUUUUUUUCAUUUUUUUUAAUGGAAAUAAGAUUUGGUCUCUCAUUUUAGGUUAAAUGAUAACUAGAAAGAUUAAACUAGACAGAUAGUUUAGGUGGAGUAUAUUUUUAAAACUCAGAACAUGUAUAUUGGUCCUGUGUUACCAAGUUUAUAUGUGACAGUUGAAAAAGAAAUUCCCUUGAAAUGAUCAUGAGGUUAAAAUUUUCUUCAUUAGGGGACUUGGAGAACCAGUAGUCGUAAGAUUAGUUGAUAGUUUCACUCCCAAGCAAUGAAUUGCUUCUGUGUGUUUCCCUGUAGGACUCAAUAGUAAAUGCUGUCUGUCUUACACAUUUAUAAGGACCCUGCAAGACGACGACAAAGGCCUUUGGCCUGUGCUACUAAACAAGAAGCCUAUGAAAAAUUUCUUCUUUAAACUUGUUUUUUCUCUUUCCAGUAAGUUCACAUUUGGAUAAUUUUAAAAAGAAAAGUAAUUACCUUUGUGUUUCCAGAACACUAUAAUUGGGGUGUAUCUUAAUUCAGUUAAAUAUUAUUAGUAGACCUGGAUUUUCCCCCUUGACCCCAUCAGUCUAUAAAGGUUAAACUGCAACUUUUAUGAAAUGGUCUUUAAUAUUUCCACAAUAAUCCUGUGCUAUAUUUGUUUUAAGAAACAAAGUAACUCUAUACACUUCAAGACUUUACAGGAUUUUUUAAAUCCUGUAUUGUUGGAUCAAUUAAUAAAGAUGCAAAAAAACUUUAUAGAGAUGUAAAAACAAAACUAUAAUGGAUCUCCUAUUUUUCUUUAAAUACAAAAAAAAAAAGGUAAAUGAACUAUUCUCCUUGUAAAGCUAAAUUCCCCAUUCUGUCUAAUAAAGGAAGACUGAAAAAAGGUUUUAAAGAACAUAAAUGGAAAGAUACAAAUGCUUUGAAGGAAUAAACGAAAUGUUAAAACAGGGUCAAUCCAUUUGAAGAAAAAGUUGGACAAAAUAAUCAGCAUUGCUCCCUCUUUUAUUUAAUAUUUGGGUACUGAUUAUAUCCACAUGGAAGUAGAAGGUAAGGAGUUUAGGAAAAUACUAGAAUCUACUCUGCUUACAUUCUUGUUUAAGUGUUUACACAGUUUGGUUCAAUUAUAAACAUUUGGCCUUUUACUAUGUUAUUUUUAUUUUGUAUGAAUACAUUAUCCUCCUUAUUUAUUUUUGUUACAUUUAUUACUUAUGUUAUUUUGUUAUGCAUUUACAACUCCAUUUUUAAAUAAAGUGUUUCUGGAACUUUA